UUUAAGACGGAUGUCUAGCAGUGCCUGAACUGUUAAGAAGCAAACGUGAGUAAAUGCCUUAGUUUCAAUAGAAAAAGAAAGUUCACAGUGGGACCUCAGAAGCAGAGGCUGUGAGAUCACCUUUCAAGAAUUGGAGGAGAAUUGCAGUAAGUGAUAGAGCCGGACGCUGAGCUGCAGCAGCCUCUGGGAAUUGGCGGGGCUGUGGCUUGUCCUGUCCUGCCGCCCCCCGCGUGGCCUCGGAAACUGUCAGAUGGUGCCUAAGGCAGAGUUGGGCAAAGAAAGAACCAGCGUUCGUUUCCUCCUGGACUCUCUAGGUCCAUGGAGCUGGUGGGGGAACGGCCCUGUCUUGCCCGAGGAGGAAAUUCGAGUCGAGCCCCCACUCCUCUCCCCGCGGGACUGAUAAACAUGUCCCUCAUUCGCCCCGGGAGGCUGGCACCCAGGCACGACGCGAGGACGGCCAGACUCGCCGACGGCGGCCGCGUCCCGGGGGGCCGGGAGCGAGCCUGUCGGAAGGUGGGAGGCGGAGUCGCUCGGCAUCUGGGAAGAGACCAAAGGAAUGAGUCAUUGGAAAUGCUGAACUGGUGCGCCUACAUCGUGAACAAGAAUGUGAGCUGCUCCGUGCUGGAGGGAAGUGAGAGUUUUAUUCAGGCUCAGUACAACUGUGCCUGGAACCAGAUGCCCUGUCCGUCGGCGCUGGUGUAUCGAGUGAACUUCAGACCUAGAUAUGUCACUAGGUAUAAGACAGUGACACAGUUGGAAUGGAGGUGCUGUCCUGGCUUUAGAGGGGGAGAUUGCCAAGAAGGUCCCAAAGACCCCGUGAAGACCCUCCGCCCCACGCCGGCUCGGCCUCGAAACAGCUUGAAGAAAGCCACAGAUAAUGAACCCAGCCAAUUCUCAGAGCCCAGGAAGACUUUGUCCCCAACUGGUACAGCACAACCAAGCUGGGGGGUAGAUCCAAAAGAGGGGCCUCAGGAACUUCAGGAAAAGAAGAUACAGGUGCUAGAGGAGAAGGUUCUUCGACUCACAAGGACGGUUCUUGACCUCCAGUCUUCCCUUGCUGGAGUGAGUGAAAAUCUCAAACAUGCCACUCAGGAUGAUGCCAGUAGAACACGGGCACCAGGGCUCAGCAGCCAGCACCCCAAGCCUGACACCACUGUUAGUGGAGACACAGAAACGGGCCAGAGUCCUGGUGUCUUCAACACUAAGGAAUCUGGCAUGAAGGACAUCAAGUCUGAAUUGGCUGAAGUCAAAGAUACUCUAAAGAACAAAAGUGACAAGCUGGAAGAGCUGGAUGGAAAAGUGAAGGGCUACGAAGGGCAGCUCAGACAGCUCCAGGAAGCAGCUCAGGGCCCGACGGUGACCAUGACAACCAACGAACUCUACCAAGCCUAUGUGGACAGUAAGAUCGACGCCCUGAGAGAGGAGCUCAUGGAGGGCAUGGACAGAAAGCUGGCUGACCUGAAAAACUCAUGUGAGUACAAGCUCACUGGCCUCCAGCAGCAGUGUGAUGACUAUGGGAGCAGCUACCUGGGAGUGAUAGAGCUCAUAGGGGAGAAGGAAACAAGCCUGAGAAAAGAAAUAAAUAACCUCCGAGCCCGGCUACAGGAGCCUUCAGCCCAGGCAAAUUGCUGCGACAGUGAAAAGAAUGGUGACAUUGGUCAACAGAUCAAGACAUUGGACCAGAAAAUCGAGAGAGUUGCUGAAGCCACCAGAAUGCUGAAUGGAAGACUGGACAAUGAGUUUGACCGCCUUAUAGUUCCAGAGCCAGAUGUGGAUUUUGAUGCAAAAUGGAAUGAACUCGAUGCAAGGAUCAAUGUGACGGAGAAGAACGCUGAAGAACAUUGCUUUUACAUUGAGGAAACCCUUCGGGGCGCCAUUAAUGGAGAGGUGGGUGACUUGAAGCAGCUUGUUGAUCAGAAAAUACAGUCUCUGGAAGACCGUCUGGGGAGCGUUCUCCUACAGAUGACCAAUAACACUGGUGCAGAGCUCAGUCCCCCAGGGGCAGCAGCCCUGCCAGGAGUGUCAGGGUCAGGAGAUGAACGGGUCAUGAUGGAAUUAAACCACCUGAAGGACAAAGUUCAAGUUGUUGAAGACAUUUGCCUGCUGAACAUCCAGGGAAAGCCUCAUGGGAUGGAAGGUGCCUUGCCAAACAGGGAAGACCGCGCAGUACGCGACAGCCUGCACCUUUUGAAAUCUCUCAACGACACGAUGCACAGGAAGUUUCAAGAAACCGAACAAACCAUCCAGAAACUUCAACAGGAUUUUAGUUUUCUUUAUUCUCAAUUAAACCACACAGAAAAUGAUGUGACUCAUCUUCAAAAGGAAAUGAGCAAUUGUAGAGCAGGUGAAAACGCUGGCAUGGGUAGGUUCACUAAGGUGGGUGAGCAAGAAAGGACAGUGGACACCCUGCCGUCCCCCCAGCACCCCGUGGCUCAUUGCUGCAGUCAGCUGGAGGAGAGGUGGCAGAGGUUGCAGAGCCAGGUCAUCUCGGAGCUGGAUGCUUGUAAGGAAUGCACGCAGGGGGUCCAGAGGGAGGUCUCCAUGGUGGAGGGCAGGGUGUCUCAUAUGGAGAAAACUUGCAGCAAGCUGGACUCUAUCUCAGGAAAUCUUCAGAGGAUCAAGGAGGGGCUCAACAAGCAUGUCAGCAGCCUGUGGAACUGUGUCAGGCAGAUGAACGGAACGCUCAGGUCGCAUUCCAGAGACAUUUCUGGCCUGAAGAAUUCAGUCCAGCAGUUCUACAGCCACGUCUUCCAGAUUUCUACUGAUUUGCAAGAUCUGGUCAAAUUUCAGCCAUCAGCAAAGGCGCCCUCGCCCCCGCCGCCCGCAGAGGCCCCGAAGGAGCCGCUGCAGCCCGAGCCCGCCCCGCCGAGGCCCAGCGGCCCCGCAACCGCAGAGGACCCUGGGCGACGGCCCGUCCUGCCCCAGCGGCCCCCCGAGGAGAGGCCGCCCCAGCCGCCAGGCUCCACCGGGGUCAUCGCGGAGACGGGCCAGGCCGGGCCCCCCGCAGGCGCAGGCGUGUCUGGGCGGGGUCUGCCGCGGGGCGUGGACGGCCAGACCGGGAGCGGCACCGUCCCCGGCGCAGAAGGCUUCGCGGGCGCACCAGGAUACCCGAAGUCACCUCCUGUAGCUUCCCCAGGAGCUCCGGUGCCUUCUCUGGUGUCUUUUUCUGCGGGGCUCACCCAGAAGCCUUUCCCCAGUGAUGGGGGCGUUGUCCUCUUUAACAAAGUGCUGGUGAACGACGGGGAUGUUUACAACCCCAGCACCGGGGUCUUCACGGCUCCUUAUGAUGGGCGCUACCUGAUCACGGCCACCCUCACCCCCGAGAGAGACGCCUACGUGGAAGCAGUGCUGUCGGUCUCCAACGCCAGCGUGGCCCAGCUGCAUACCGCUGGGUACAGGAGAGAGUUCCUGGAAUACCACCGCCCUCCAGGAGCUUUGCAUACCUGCGGGGGCCCGGGGGCAUUCCACCUCAUCGUGCACCUGAAGGCGGGAGAUGCAGUCAACGUCGUGGUGACUGGGGGCAAGCUGGCUCACACAGACUUUGAUGAAAUGUACUCCACAUUUAGUGGGGUUUUCUUAUAUCCUUUCCUUUCCCACCUCUAAGGUGGCUGGGGAGAUGUCAGGGGAAAGAUAGAUAGUUGUAAAAACUCUAAAGCUUUAAUAUAUUCGGUUUGUAUGUAAUGGAAGCACGGGGCUAGAGUUUCCACAUAGGCCCCAACAUAAAGGCCUUCCCUCGCUGUUGAGGCCACCAUGCCUUACUGCAUCCAGCCAGGCUGCAGGGAGUGAGGCACACGGUGAACAUGGCCACUGACUUUUCUGCCACUCUAACUGGACAACUGGAAGACUUGGAAAGGCCUCCACCUGUAUCUACACUCUGAGGGCCCUGGACUGGGCCUGAGCUUGCCACAGAGGCUCCGUCUGACUGUGGGCUGGGAGGAGGGAGGCAGGGGAGAGCCGGUCACGGUGGCUGGUCUUUACUGCAGGGCAGCACUGUGGCCAGCUGUCUGUCUUUACACUGCAUGCAGAAGUUUAAACACUGAAGUGCCGAAGUGGCCCGUGCCGCCGCACAGAGACCCCGACUUUAGUUUGGGCUGUUCCACGCUUGGCUCACCAUUGCCGCCUGGGACUUAACCUGCUCAGGCGGGCCUUCGCCCAGCUGCAAAUAGGGAUGCGUUAGAGACUGUUCCCAAAGCUUGUUGGGCUCCUUAAAUGGCAUGUACAAUUUAAGUGCAAAGACAGGGAGUGUCAAUAAAGAUGGAAAGCCAUUUCCAGUUAACUUUUGUUAAUUUAAGUGUGGUCCCUUACAGAUCGGGAGUUGUUGCUAAAAAGCAAACUGAAGAAAUGUUUUGUUUCAAAAAGGGCUACAGAAAGUAACCUUGAGUAAAAUUAAUCUCAGCUACAAAACUGUUACCCCUCCGCAUCCAAGCUAUACACUUGGGUUUUGUUUCUGGCUUGUGAAGACGGACCAGAUGUGCACGGAGGUCAAGGCCCCAUGUCAUCUGCAGCUGGAGCGGCUCCUCUGGGGAUGCUGCACUCAGAUCCCACAGCAGCUGCCCAGGCUAACUUGAUCCCUGCUGCUUCACUGCACCAAUCUCCAGCAGACACAGCUCGCCGAGCUCUUGGGUUUCUAAGCAGCAGGAAGCUCAACCUAACGCUGGCCACACGCUGACAGCUGAGCCCAUCUGAGAACACGGCAUCUUCACACAGCGAGACGCCUCCACUGAGGGGAGGCCCGGGAGUAUCAAUCUGUCACCAGUGGCCACGGAGACCUCUCAGCACCCUUAGUUCAAGGUAGUCUCUGUGGAUCAGGUUGGUAACACCUACUGGUUAAUCAAGUCCCACUGGGGAAAGGUUUGGACGGUAGAAUCAAGAGCUGCAGUUUCCUUGGCCCACAAGAUGCUCUUAUGCUGUAAAAAAAAUGCUUUAAGAAUUGUUUGCAAAUGAAUUUACAGGGUGGCCACUGGACACUUCAGAGUUCCUUAUUUACUCCCCCCGCCACAGCUAGGAAGACCAGCAAGAACUAAAGGUUUGCCGUUUUACUAUUUAAAAUGUGGACCUCUUUGUCCAGGAGCGGGAGGGAGAAUGGCAUCUCACCCCAUUACAACAGCUGGGGAACUGGCUAAAGAGAGCUGUCAGAGAGUAUCCUUGGCUGUCCUAGGAAUGACUCAUGGAAAGCGCCCCAGUGCAGCAGUGUUUUCAGGAAAACCCAGUGGGCACGCGCCAUCGCCCUCUCCUCUCCUCUCACGCUCCUUUUGAAAAGACCGCACUCGGCGCCCAAGGGGACGUGCUCAAGAGCUGCAGGGGCAGGGCCCAGGCAAAAGGUGGGUGAUGACUACCUGCUGCUUUCCCUACUCCGUAGAUGGGUCUGGAACAUCGGGUAAAACCCAGUCCUCCUCUCAGUGCAUCUCUACUCACCAACAAUGGUGAAUCUCAGCUCUGUGUAUUCAAGACAGGCAAAACAGAAUAUGCCUCAUUAUGGCUGGAGCGUGCCUCUACUUUGAGAUAAAGCUGGAUGACAGGUGGAUCCUGGCCCACUUAGGAGACAUCUUUAGAAAGGGAAAGGCUGUCUUUUUGUACAGGUAGUAGAACAACAAGGUCAGCUGAGCUUAAGGCUGUGGGGUUCGAAGCAGCCCUUCAAGAAGUCAUCACCCCUGAAGUAGUGCCUGCGAGUCAGUCAGAGGCAUACCAAACCCUGAGACAGAAUCAGGCACAAGUUCACAACUUUUUUUUUUUUUUGGGGGGAGACAGUCCUACUCUGUCGCCCAGGCUGGAGUGCAGUAGCGCGAUCUCAGCUCACUGCAACCUCCGCCUCCCGGGUUCAAGCAAUUCUCCUACCUCAGCCUCCCGAGUAGCGGGGACUACAGGUGCAUGCCGCCACGCCCGGUUAAUUUUUUGUAUUUUAGUAGAGAUGGGGUUUCACCGUGUUGCCCAGGCUGGUCGCGAACUCCUGAGCUCAGCCAAUCCGCCCACCUCGGCCUCCCAAAGUGCUGGGAUUACAGGUAUGAGCCACCACGCCCAGCCAAGUUCACAACUUCUGAUAUCAAGUUGUUGCUGAGAAAAGGUCAGGACACUUCUUAAGUAGAGAAGGACUGUGACAUCCCCUCCAAACCUCCAUGUAACACUAACAAAUGGCCUCAUUUACACGAUUAAAAACAAAAUGGUAUCGUCAAUAAAUGCAAACCUUAAACUGCAUUUGAAAUUA